AGCCUCAAGGUCGGCGAUACCCUGAGCAUUCGGGCCCCCGCCUGCAGGACUCGCUCCUGCCAGCCAAGGACUCAAGAAGGAGGGAGUCCCCAGUCCCGGCGGGGCGCCUGGGAUUCGGUUCAAUAUUUAGCACAGUCAGUACCGAAGCAGGGGCAGCCAGGUGGGAGCUGGGCGCCCAAAAGUUGGACCCCAAUCAGCAGCGAGUGGGCAGCGGGGGCCUGGCUCGCCCGCGCCCGCGCCCCGGAGCUCUCCGGCUGGCUCUCUGCUCCCCGAAGCUGGGGAGCCGGGGGCGCUCUCCCGGGCCGCAAGCAGGCACGGAAUUUGACGCCCGAGAGGCAGAUGGUCCUGGCUAGGACUCCUGAUUCUUCUCAGAUGGAAACAGUUUCUCCCGGUGAACCUGCCGGAAUUCUCAGUGGACUCGAUCUUCAGCUUUGUCCACUGGCGCAUUUCACCAAGGCCGCAUUUACCGCUUUGAGGCAAAUUUGAGCUUCAAAUGGAGCGGGACUCCUGGUUGCAGAACGAGGGUGUGGGAAUGCGCAUCUGCAAGACCAGAGGAUGCAGAGCUUGCAGGAAGGAGGAAACUCACUAGGUUCAGGUUCAUGAAAUUUUCAGGAAUUAAAGUUAGUCCUGAGGAAAGUUCAUGAAUGUCUAAUGCUGGACUGUGAUUCUUGCUGAGAGAACUACAAAAGGAUGGACUCCAGCAAGAGGAAAAAUGAAUCUAAGGAAUGGAGUGGGAUAUAAGCAAUAACAGUGAGGAGGAGGAAGAGAAGCAGAAGAGCAGCUGGAGGCCGGCGGUGGCUGAGCAGCCCCCACACCUUUGAGCGAGCCGCCUGCCUCUCCACCGGCAAGGAAGCCCUGGGACCUCCGGAUUCGGGCUGCCGGAGGGCCUGAGCGCCAGAGCCCAGGACCCGGCGGCCGGGGGCGCCAUCCCCUCAUGUUCUGGAGAAGGCGCAAAUGUGAGCUGGCGGUAGCGGGGAAAGCCCUCCGCCCCCGCCAGGGGGGACCCGGGAAGCCCGGCCGGCUCUGUCGGCAGACUGCGGGGAUCCCCUCCUCCGGCCCCGCCCCCACCCACCCCCGGCCGGGGUGCCGAGGCGGUUAACCCUACCCGCGCCGCAGCGCACUUGGGCUAGAGCGCCGCGCACCCAAUCCAGAUUCCAGAGCCUGCCGGCUGGGAAAGAUCCGGUCUCGGGGUCGGCUAUGAUCCCGCAGCGGCCAAGGCAGGGCUCAGGCCCCGGGAUUCUCCCCACACGCUGCUGCACUGGCGCAGCCGGUCGCCAAACUUUUUCUCCCCAAAGCCAGUGCCCCCGCAGUUACUUGGCGGGCAGCCGGCAGCCCACUCUCGGCGGGAUGAUCUGGGAGAAGCGGGCGUGGGACGAGGGGGCUGCUGUUUUGCAGCCCUGCGAGGCGUGCAGUCGGAGAAGUGGUCGGGGUUCCACACCGUCCCUGAGCCUGCCCCCGGCCAAGGUGGCCCGACGUGCUGCAGUGGCUGGCGCAGGUGAUCCGGGCAGCGCGUCCGGCACUAGUCAAGGGGGCAGCGGCACGGGAGGGAGGGGCGCCUUUCUCUUUUCUCCUCCCCCUGCAGCCCAGCUGCACUGCGUGGGGGCUCUCCAUCUCCACGCAAUCAGCAGGCGGAAUCCCUGCCCUGGAGCGCCCUGGCUCUGGACUGCACCCCCCUAGGGUUUGUCCUGCAGAUUCCCCUCCCCAUCUUUCUCUGCCACACACGCUUCCCUAAGCCGCGCGCGCCGCAAACUCAGUCUCGGUCCCCGCAGGUGAUGUCAUGCCCAUUGUUUUGGUGCGCCCAACCAAUCGGACUCGCCGCCUGGAUUCUACCGGAGCCGGCAUGGGCCCUUCCUCGCACCAGCAGCAGGAGUCCCCGCUCCCGACCAUAACGCAUUGCGCAGGGUGCACCACCGCUUGGUCUCCCUGCAGCUUUAACAGCCCUGACAUGGAAACCCCAUUGCAGUUCCAGCGCGGCUUCUUCCCAGAGCAGCCGCCGCCGCCGCCGCGCUCCUCACACCUGCAUUGCCAGCAGCAGCAACAGAGCCAGGACAAGCCGUGCCCGCCCUUCGCGCCCCUCCCGCACCCUCACCACCACCCGCACCUCGCGCACCAGCAGCCGGCCAGCGGCGGCAGCAGCCCAUGCCUCCGGUGCAACAGCUGCGCCUCCUCCGGUGCCCCGGCGGCGGGGGCGGGAGAUAACCUGUCCCUGCUGCUCCGCACCUCCUCGCCCGGCGGCGCCUUCCGGACCCGCACCUCCUCGCCGCUGUCGGGCUCGUCCUGCUGCUGCUGCUGCUGCUCGUCGCGCCGGGGCAGCCAGCUCAAUGUGAGCGAGCUGACGCCGUCCAGCCAUGCCAGUGCGCUCCGGCAGCAGUACGCGCAGCAGUCCGCGCAGCAGUCGGCGUCCGCCUCCCAGUACCACCAGUGCCACAGCCUGCAGCCCGCCGCCAGCCCCACGGGCAGCCUCGGCAGUCUGGGCUCCGGGCCCCCGCUCUCGCACCACCACCACCACCCGCACCCGGCGCACCACCAGCACCACCAGCCCCAGGCGCGCCGCGAGAGCAACCCCUUCACCGAAAUAGCCAUGAGCAGCUGCAGGUACAACGGGGGCGUCAUGCGGCCGCUCAGCAACUUGAGCGCGUCCCGCCGGAACCUGCACGAGAUGGACUCAGAGGCGCAGCCCCUGCAGCCCCCCGCGUCUGUCGGAGGAGGUGGCGGCGCGUCCUCCCCGUCUGCAGCCGCUGCCGCCGCCGCCGCUGUUUCGUCCUCAGCCCCCGAGAUCGUGGUGUCUAAGCCCGAGCACAACAACUCCAACAACCUGGCGCUCUAUGGAACCGGCGGCGGAGGCAGCACUGGAGGAGGCGGCGGCGGUGGCGGGAGCGGGCACGGCAGCAGCAGUGGCACCAAGUCCAGCAAAAAGAAAAACCAGAACAUCGGCUACAAGCUGGGCCACCGGCGCGCCCUGUUCGAAAAGCGCAAGCGGCUCAGCGACUACGCGCUCAUCUUCGGCAUGUUCGGCAUCGUGGUCAUGGUCAUCGAGACCGAGCUGUCGUGGGGCGCCUACGACAAGGCGUCGCUGUAUUCCUUAGCUCUGAAAUGCCUUAUCAGUCUCUCCACGAUCAUCCUGCUCGGUCUGAUCAUCGUGUACCACGCCAGGGAAAUACAGUUGUUCAUGGUGGACAAUGGAGCAGAUGACUGGAGAAUAGCCAUGACUUAUGAGCGUAUUUUCUUCAUCUGCUUGGAAAUACUGGUGUGUGCUAUUCAUCCCAUACCUGGGAAUUAUACAUUCACAUGGACGGCCCGGCUUGCCUUCUCCUAUGCCCCAUCCACAACCACCGCUGAUGUGGAUAUUAUUUUAUCUAUACCAAUGUUCUUAAGACUCUAUCUGAUUGCCAGAGUCAUGCUUUUACAUAGCAAACUUUUCACUGAUGCCUCCUCUAGAAGCAUUGGAGCACUUAAUAAGAUAAACUUCAAUACACGUUUUGUUAUGAAGACUUUAAUGACUAUAUGCCCAGGAACUGUACUCUUGGUUUUUAGUAUCUCAUUAUGGAUAAUUGCCGCAUGGACUGUCCGAGCUUGUGAAAGGUACCAUGAUCAACAGGAUGUUACUAGCAACUUCCUUGGAGCGAUGUGGUUGAUAUCAAUAACUUUUCUCUCCAUUGGUUAUGGUGACAUGGUACCUAACACAUACUGUGGAAAAGGAGUCUGCUUACUUACUGGAAUUAUGGGUGCUGGUUGCACAGCCCUGGUGGUAGCUGUAGUGGCAAGGAAGCUAGAACUUACCAAAGCAGAAAAACACGUGCACAAUUUCAUGAUGGAUACUCAGCUGACUAAAAGAGUAAAAAAUGCAGCUGCCAAUGUACUCAGGGAAACAUGGCUAAUUUACAAAAAUACAAAGCUAGUGAAAAAGAUAGAUCAUGCAAAAGUAAGAAAACAUCAACGAAAAUUCCUGCAAGCUAUUCAUCAAUUAAGAAGUGUAAAAAUGGAGCAGAGGAAACUGAAUGACCAAGCAAACACUUUGGUGGACUUGGCAAAGACCCAGAACAUCAUGUAUGAUAUGAUUUCUGACUUAAACGAAAGGAGUGAAGACUUCGAGAAGAGGAUUGUUACCCUGGAAACAAAACUAGAGACUUUGAUUGGUAGCAUCCACGCCCUCCCUGGGCUCAUAAGCCAGACCAUCAGGCAGCAGCAGAGAGAUUUCAUUGAGGCUCAGAUGGAGAGCUACGACAAGCACGUCACUUACAAUGCUGAGCGGUCCCGGUCCUCGUCCAGGAGGCGGCGGUCCUCUUCCACAGCACCACCAACUUCAUCAGAGAGUAGCUAGAAGAGAAUAAGUUAACCACAAAAUAAGACUUUUUGCCAUCAUAUGGUCAAUAUUUUAGCUUUUAUUGUAAAGCCCCUAUGGUUCUAAUCAGCGUUAUCCGGGUUCUGAUGUCAGAAUCCUGGGAACCUGAACACUAAGUUUUAGGCCAAAAUGAGUGAAAACUCUUUUUUUUUCUUUCAGAUGCACAGGGAAUGCACCUAUUAUUGCUAUAUAGAUUGUUCCUCCUGUAAUUUCACUAACUUUUUAUUCAUGCACUUCAAACAAACUUUACUACUACAUUAUAUGAUAUAUAAUAAAAAAAGUUAAUUUCUGCA